AGUUUCCCAGCAGGGCUCACAGCAGCGUUCCGCGUCAUGGGGAUUUGGCAGCGUCUGCUGCUUUUUGGUGGGGUGUCGCUCCGGGCUGGUGGCGGGGCCACUGCCCCGCUUGGGGGAAGCCGAGCGAUGGUUUGUGGGCGCCAGUUGUCUGGCGCCGGGAGUGAGACCCUAAAACAAAGAAGAACACAAAUCAUGUCCCGAGGACUUCCAAAGCAGAAACCGAUAGAAGGUGUUAAACAAGUUAUAGUUGUGGCUUCUGGAAAGGGUGGAGUCGGAAAAUCUACUACAGCAGUGAAUCUUGCACUUGCACUAGCAGCGAACGAUUCGUCCAAGGCCAUUGGUUUGCUAGAUGUGGAUGUGUAUGGACCUUCAGUUCCAAAGAUGAUGAAUCUGAAAGGAAAUCCGGAAUUAUCACAGAGCAACCUAAUGAGGCCUCUCUUGAAUUAUGGUAUUGCUUGUAUGUCUAUGGGCUUUCUGGUUGAAGAAAGUGAACCAGUAGUUUGGAGAGGCCUUAUGGUAAUGUCGGCCAUUGAGAAAUUGUUGAGGCAGUGUUAUAUGAGAGUUAGCCUGGCCUCAAAAAGUAAGUUGGAAAGUACUUUCCUCUUCUGUUUUGUGAAAUAUCUUGUGUAAAAAAUUUAUUAGCUUUGGUUUAAAUGUUGGUAUUUGAAGGAAUUUAUCGGUGAAACCCAGGCUUGGCGUGCUUUGUUUUGUUUUGGGUUGGUAGAACAUUUUUGAUGACUAAUUCUAUUCAGAUUUUAAAUUUUAUCUUGUUUUAAUUAUGUUAAAUUGUGUUUUAUAGGAAUUUGUUUCUUUUACUUUAAUUGUAUAAUGUACACAUGAAAUUUGUUCAUAAUAUUUUCUUAUGUUUUUAAAUGGAUAUGGGAUGUAGCAGUGUUCCCUCCUUAUUUCUAAUGUUAGUAAUUUGUUUAUUUUUCUCUUUUAUUCUUGAUUGUUCUUGCCAGAUGUUUAUAAACUUUACUGGUUUUUUUUUUCAAAAAAACCGACUUUUCACCCUUAGACGUUUUUCUGUCAUAUGUUUGUUUCUUAUUUCAUUGUUUCUGCUUUUAUCAUUAUUAUUUCCUUCCUUUCAUUUGUAUCAGGCUAAUAUACCCUUCUUUUUCUAGCUCUUAAGGUAGGCAGUUAAAUAAUUGAUUUAAAUUUUUUUUUAAAUACAAGCAGUUAAGGCUAUAAAUUUAUCUCUUAGGCGUUGCUUAAACUUUCACAAAUUCUGAUACGUUGGUGUUUUCAUUGUCAUUCAGUUAAAAGUAGUUUCUAAUUUCCUUCUUUUGCCUACAAAUAUUUUUGGUAUGUUGUUUAAUAUCUGAACAUUGGAAGAUCUUCUUAAUAACUUAAUGGCAUUGAUUUCUAGUGUAAUUUUGUUUUGGCUAGAGAAUACACUCUGUAAUAUUUCAGUGUUAAAAUGUUUUGAGAUUUUCUUUUUGUGGACCAGCACCAGCAUGCGAUCCAUCUUUGUGAAUAUUUCAUACGCUUUUGGAACGACUGCAUUUUUAAAUUAUUUUGGUUAAUGUUCUUUAAAUAUGAUUUAGGUCAGGUUGGUUGACAGAGUUCACAUUUUUUUGUAACUUUAUUGAUUUGUCUAGUUACUGUAUAAAUUAAUGAGAGAGGAGUGUUAACAUCUCCAGGUAUGAUUGUAUAUUUGCCCAUUUCUCUCUCUAUUUCAAUUUUUACUUAAUAUAUUUUGGAGUUCUGUUAUACUCUCAUAUGUUUUGAAUUGUUAUGUAUUCGUGGUGAAUUUGCCCUUUUGUUGUUAUGAAAUACUCCUCUAUAUCUCUGGUAAAUUCUUCAUAUUGAAGUCUACUUUAUCUGAUACUAAUAUAGCCACAUUUGCUUUUCUUAUGCAUAUAAUUUCAUGGAAUGUUUUAAUUCUUUUACUUUUAACCUUCUAUUUCAUUAUAUUUAAAGUGAGUCUCUUGAUUUCAACAUUUAGUUGUAUCUUACUGUUUUAUCCAGUUUGAUAAUCUUUGCCUUUUAAUUGGAAUGCUUAGUUUAUUUACAUUUAGUAUAAUUAUUAAUGGUUGGGUUUCAGUCUACCAUUUUGAUUUUUUCCUCAUAUGUUUCAUCUGUUUUUUUCUUUUUUCUUACGUUCUUUGAAUAAAUGAAAUAUUUCUUGAAUUCCAUUUAAAUUCUCCAUUAGGUCCUUAGCUAUCUAUCCCUCUUGGUAUUAUUAUUCUAUGACUGCUUUAGGGAUUAUAAUAUGUUUUCUUAUCACAGCCUUCUUAAAGAAAAGUUAAUAUUGUGCUAUUUAAUAUGUAGUUAAGAAUGCUGUGUCUCAGUCCAUUUAGUGUUGCUAUAAAGGAAUACCUGAGGCUGGGUAAUUUAUAAAGAAAAGAGGUUUAUUUGGCUCAUGGUUCUACAGACUGUACAAGAAGCAUGGCACCAACAUCUGCUUCUGGUGAAGGUUUCAGGCUGCUCCCACUCAUGGUGGAAGGCAAAGGAGAGCCAGUAUAUGCAGAGAUCACCUGACAAGAGAGAGGAAGUGAGGCGGGGAGGAGGUGCUAGGUUCCUUUUUUUUUUUUUUUUUGACAACGAGCUCUUGUAGAAACUAAUAGAGUGAGAACUCUCAUUACUUUAAGGAUGGCACCAAGCUGUUUAUGAGGGAUCCUCUUCCAUGACCCAAGAACCUCCCACUAGAUUCCACCUCCAACAUUGGAGAUACAAUUUCAACAUGAGGUUUAGAGAGACAUCUAUCCAAACUAUAGCACCCUGUAACAAUACAGUACCAUUCACCAUCUCCUAUAUUUUAUUGUGAUAUAUUUUAACUAUACAUCCAUUAUAAAUCUCACAUACAGUGCUAUAAAACUUAUUUAAUCAUCUUUUAAGCUAGUUAAUAAAACAAUCUUUUUUUUUUUUUUUUUUUUUUUGUGAGACAGGGUCUCACUCUGUCACUAUGCUGUAGCUCAAUGGCAUAAUCUAGGCUCACUGCAACUUCCGCCUCCUUGGUUCAAGCAGUUCUCCUGCCUCAGCCUCCCAAGUAGCUGGGAUUACAGGCCACCACAUCCAGCUAAUUUUUGUAUUUUUAGUAGAGACGGAGUUUCACCAUUUUGGCUAGGAUGGUCUCGAUCUCCUGACCUCGUGAUCUGCCCGCCUCAGCCCCCCAAAGUGCUGGGAUUACAGGCGUGAGCCACCGCGCCCGGCUGCCAAAACAAUCUUUUUUAUUUACCUACACACUUGCUAUUUCAGUACUUUUCAAUUUUUCUUUAGAUCUGAGUUUAAUCUGGUACUGUUUUUCUUUAUCUUAAAAAUCUUCAUUUUUUUUCUAUGUUGUGGGUCUGCUGGUGAUGAAUUUUCUCAGUUUUUAUUUAUUGGAAAUGUCUUUAUUUUUCCCUCCUUAUUUUCACUGCAUAUAGAAUUUUGAGUUGACAUUUUAAAUUCAAGUCUUAAAUGAUGUUCCACUGUCCUCUGGCCUUCAACUGCUACUACCAUAGUAGUAGUUUCUUUAGUUGUUCUGUGAGUAAGGUGGUUUUUUCUCUGGCAGUUUUCAUAAUUUCCUUGAUAUCUUUGGGUCAUUUUUCUUGCCUAUCCCUUAAAUAUUGAUGCUUUCCAGAAUUACAUCCAUAGCUCAAUAGCUAAGGGCAUGGACUCAGAAGUCACAUCUGCCUGAGUUUAUUCCAUUUUCAAUAUCUAAUAGCUGUGUGACCUUGGGCAGAAACUUCUCUGAGCUUUUGUUUUCUCAUCUGUAAAUGGGGUUGAUGGUAGUUACCUCAUCAUGGGGAUUAAAUGAGUUAAUAUGUGUCAUAUGCUUAGGAAACCUAGUGUCAUGUACAUGGGUUUUGUAAUUAUUUUAUUUUGUCUGGGUAUACUUUUUUUUCACAUUUUAACUUAUCUUCAAUUAAGAUGUAUUUUGCAAUUGAUGGCUUUUCAGCAUUGCUUUAUCCCUGUAUUGAAGUGGGGUCCUUUCAGAAAGGUUUUGUAUCGUUUUUGCAGUCACCUGGAAUGCUUUAACCUGAGGCACUUUCAAUUUAAUUAUCCGUUAGAAGUUUUGGGGACCACUCUGGUGGUAUGAAUACAGAUCGGAAAGCUGCAUGUAUACCAACUGGUGGUUCAUGUUGUUAAGGAGGUGUUUUCUCCCCUCUGCCAUGGCCCAAGUUGAGAGAUUUCUUUCUAAAUUGUGGAUUUAUAUAUUAUUUAUCUUUGGUUUAAGAUGAUGUAGUCCUUUGGGAUCCUAGCUUUAUGUAGGAUUCUCCUAUUAGACCCCAAUUUAUCUUAGGUGUUUUUUUCGUUUAGUGCUACACAAAAUAAUGAUGCAUCUUAUAAUUAGUGGUGUAUUAGAUUUGUUGAUGUUAUAAUGGGUAUCAACAUUGUUACCAGCAUUAUCCCUGAGACACCUCUUCUGUCAUGGCUUGAAUUAAUGUUGAUUAUAGUAAGGGAAAGUAAUGAAUUGAGGACUUCUCUUUGGUUAACAUUCAUAUUUGGAGGUGUGUGAUUUAGUGGGAGGAAAAGGAGUUAGUAAACAGGAAAAGAAGUAGUUCAAAAGGUAGGAAAAAACUAAGGAUACUAAUGUCAUGAAGAUUAAAGGUUUGGAGCAAUGGUUUUCCAACAUAUCUGUAUAUUAGAAUCAUCUAGGGAUUUUAAACAAUUUUCAAAUUUCAGCUCACACCUCAGACCAAUUAAAUUACAAAUCCUGGGCAUGUGACCCAGGCAUUAUCACUUUUGGAACUGUCCACCUGAUUCCAGUCUGUGGACAAGUUUGGGAAUCACUGGUGUGGAGAGUUUUAAGAAUGAUAGGUCAGGGAGAACAAGGAUUGAGAUAGGGCAAGGGAAUAAUAGAUGUUCGGUGGAAAUUUGUAAACCUUAACUAGAACAGGGAAUGAAAAAAGAUUAUAGGGGUUUAAGAAUACAUUUAUAACAAUACUAUGUAGGUAGAGGUGUAUUCUACCUAUAUAGAGAGUAUUGUAUUCUAAAAUAGGCCAUUCAAGAAUUUGGGGGCUGGGUGAGGGAAAGGAAAGGAAAAUAGGAUGGUAGCUUAAGGAGGAGUGGUAUAUUAAAUUAAAGCCUUUUUUUUUCUUAAAGAGGACAGCCAUACCUUUUACAAGGUGAAAGGAUUCAGUGAAGAGGCAGUGAAAAUUAUAGAAAAUGAGAGGAUUGUUUUAAAAAAUUAUGAAAAAGGCAAAAGGGAAUAGGAUUAAAGGUCAGAGAGGUAAGUUAUUUUUGAAAAAGAAGUUCUUCCAAAUUUGUGUUUGGAAUAGAAAAAAAGGGCAGAUAAAGUAAUCCCAUCCUACCUGACACUAAAAAGAAGUUAACAAAAGGUAUUCUUCCCAGUAGACGGGAAAAGAUGGUGCAUUUAUUCAAUAGAGCAGUGAUGCACAGUUUUUAGUGUUCAUGAAAAUUACAUGGAGAACUGAUUUAAAAUUCAAAUUUAUAGGCUUUCUAUUCCACUCUCCCACUUGAAGAUUUUUAUUCAGUAGGUCCCAGGUAUGGCCAAGGAAUUCACAUUUUAAUUAGAUUAUUCCAGGUGACUCUAAUGCUGGUGGGUCUAAAAUCAGGCUUAGGCAUACAAUGGUACAGAGGCAGUUCUUUUUAACUGCUUUCAGAGGAAUUAAAAAAAAGAGAGAUGAGGAGAUGAAUGAUAAGACCCCUGUGUAGCAGCAAAGGCCUACUGGAUGCUGAAUAUCAAAAUUUUUACUUUUGCCAAGUUUUUAUGACUGUUUUCAAUAACUCUUUGAAGCCUGCAAGGUGACAUGGGUAAACCUUUUGUUAGAUCUAGGAUUAGUAACUGGUGUGGCAGAAAGUCCAAAGGAGAAAAAUAUCCAGGGAAUUAAUGAGUGGAACACUGAAGUCCUGGUUUCAAGAAAGACAGGUAGUCAAGAGGGAUCAGGAGACUGGGUAAAAUUGGAGAGAUCAAAUAUGAAACACCUGGAAUGAGGAAGAAGCAAUUCAGUAGCUGGUAGAAGAAAAGGUGUGAAAAGUGAUGGAUAAGUUGGUUGUGUUCAGAGGAGGGAUAUUAGAAACUUAGGCUUUUCUAAAAAAUAAAAGAAUUUGGAAAUGAGGUUAUGUGAGGAAAAUCAGGUCUCUAGCAAAGCAAUAAAAAUGUCAAGGAUCAAAGUAUCACACACUGGGAGCAGGGUUGCCAGGUAAUAUGUUGGAUGCCCAGUUAAGUUUGAGCAUCAGACACGCAAUGAAUAAUUUGGGAUCUGCCUUUUCUCCAUAUCCUCGCCAGCAUUUGCUAUUGCUUUUCAUAACAACAUGGAAUGCUUCACAAAUUUAUGUGUCAUCCUUGUGCAGGGGCCAUGCUAAUUUUCCCUGUAUCAUUUCAAUUUUAGUAUAUGUGCUGCUGAAGUGAGCACUUGGGAUCUGUCCAUACUAAAAUAUUAUUCAGUAUGGCUGGGCACUGUGGCUCACACCUGUAAUCCCAGUGCUUUGGAAGACCAAGGUAGGAAGAUCACUUGAGGCCAGGCGUUUGAGACCAACACGUGCGACAUCGCAAGACUCUAUCUCUACAAAAAAUAAAAAACAGCUGGGCAUGGUUGCAUGUACCAGUAGUCUUGCUAUUUGGGAGGCUGAGAUGGGAGGACUGGUUGAGCCUAGGAAUUUGAGAUUGAAGUGAGCUGUGAUCAUGCUGCUGCACUCCAGCCUGGGCAACAGAGUGAGACCCUGUUUCAAAAAAAAAAUUCAUUGUGUAUCUCAUAUUCAGGCAUAAAUGACUUUGAGUUUCCUGUAUAACUGUGUUUGAACUGUUUGAGUCCACUUAUAUGAGGAUUUUUUUCAGUUAACCACAUUGGAAAAUUUUUUGCAGAUUUGGAACAACUUGAAAAAACUUGCAGAUGAACCAUGUAUCUUAGAAAUAUCAAAAAAUUAAUAAAACAUCACAUAUGUCAUGAAUGCCUAAAAUAUAUGUUGAUACUAGUGUAUUUUAUCAUGUACUACCUAAAGUAUACACAAAUCUAUUAUAAAAGUUAAAAUUUAUCAAAACUUAUGCAUACAAAACUUACACACUGUGCAUGGUGCCAUUAGCAGUCAAGAGAAAUGUAAACAAAUGUACAGAUGUAGUACUACGUUAUAACUGCAUAAAAUUCACUGUACUACAUACUAUACUGCUGUGAUAAUUUUGUUAGCUACCUCCUGUUGCUAUUGUGGUGAGCUCAAGUGUUGUGAGUAUCCACUUAAAAUGCUGUGUGCUAAUGAUCUCUGCGUGAGCAGUUCAUUUCUCCAAUCAAUUAUUACAGUAAAAAGUUAUGUCUUAGAGUUUUCAUGUAUUUUUCAUUGUGUUUAACAUAAUACCGUGAACCUUGAAUAACACCAUGGGACCAUGUGAAGUGCCACUAGUGAUGCUGGAAGUCUCUGAAGAAGUAGAGGAAAAUCACAACAUUACAAAAAAAAGUUGAAUUGCUUGAUAUGUACCAUAGAAUGAAGUCUGCAGCUGCAGUUGCUUGCCAUUUCAAGAUAAAUGAAUCCAACCUAAGGACCAUUGUGAGAAAAGAUAAGAAAAUUUGUGAAGUUGUUGCUGCAGCUACAUUAUCAGGCAUGAAAACCUUGCACAUUUUGCCAAAUACCUUUUUACUUUGUAUUGAAAAUGCAGCUUAUAUAUGAGUGCAGGAUUGCUAUAGUAAAGCAUGCCUGUAGACUCUAAUAUUAUUCAAGAAAAAAAUGAAGUCAUUAUAUAACAACUUAAAGCAAAAGAUAGCUGAAGAAUCUAAAGGUGGAGAAUUUAAUGCCAGCAAAGUAUGGUUUGAUAAUUUUAGGAAGAGGUUUCCCUUAAAAAAAUAUCAAUGUAACAGGAGAGGCAGUUUCUGCCAGCCAAGAGGCAGCAGAUGAGUUCGUGGACAUCAUUAAGUAAAUCACUGGGCCAGGCGCGGUGGUUCACGCCUGUAAUCCCAGCACUUUGGCAGGCCGAAGUGGGCAGAUCAUGAAGUCAGGAGUUUGAGACCAGCCUGGCCAACAUAGCAAAACCCCGUCUCUACUAAAAAUACAAAAAGUUAGCCAGGCGUGGUGGUGGGCGCCUGUAAUCCCAGCUACUCGGGUGGCUGAGGCAGGAGAAUCGCUCGAACCUAGAAGGCCGAGGAGGUUGCAGUGAGCUGAGAUUGCGCCAUUGCACUCCAGCCCGGGCAACAGUGUGAGACUCCAUCUCAAAGAAAAAAAAGAAAAAAAAAAAAAAAAGAAAAUCUUUGAGGAGAAAGGCUAUCUGCCUGAACAGGUUUUUGUUGUUGUUUUUUUUUUUUUUUAACUUUUAGGUUCAGGGGUUCAGAUAAGGGUUUGUUAUAUAGGUAAACUCAUUUCAGGGGGGUUUGUUGUACAGAUUAUUUCAUCACCCAGGUACUAAGCCUAGUACCCAAUAAUUAUUUUUCUUUUCCUCUCCCUCCUCCCGCCCUCCACCCUCAAGUAGGCCCCAGUGUCUGUUGUUCCUCUCUUUGUGUCCAUGUGUUCUCAUCAUUUAGCUCCUACUUAAAAGUGAAAACACGUGGUAUUUGGUUUUCUGUUCCGGCAUUAGGUUGCUAAGGAUAGUGGCCUACAGCUCCAUCCAUGUUCCUGCAAGAGACCUGAUCUCAUUUUUUUUUUUUGUGGCUGCAUUGUAUUCCAUGGUGUAUAUGUACCAUCUUUUCUUUAUUCAGUCUACCAUUGAUAGGCAUUUAGGUUGAUUCCGUGCCUUUGCUAUUGUGAAUAGUGCUGCAGGGAACAUACAAGUGCAUGUGUCUUUAUGGUAGAAUGAUUUAUAUUCUUUAGGGUAUAUACCCAGUAAUGGGAUUGUUGGGUUGAAUGGUAGUUUUGUUUAGCUCUUUGAAGAAUCACCAUACUGCUUUCCACAAUGGUUGAGCUAAUUUACACUCCCAUCAACAGUGUAUAUAUAAGUGUUCCCUUUUCCCCCCACCCUUGCCAGCAUCAGUUAUUUUUUGACAUUUUAAUAAUAGCCAUUCUGACUGGUGUGAGAUACUGUCUCAUUGUGGUUUUGAUUUGCAUUUCCUUAAUGAUCAGUGAUGUUGAGCUUUUAUUCAUAUGCUUGUUGGCUACACAUAUGUCUUCUUUUGAUAAGUGUUCAUGUCCUUUGCCCACUUUUUAAUGGAGUUUUUUUUUCUUGUAAAUUUGUUUAAGUUCCUUACAGAUGCUGGAUAUUAGACCUUUGUCAGAUGCAUAGUUUGUGAAUAUUUUCUCUCAUUCUGUAGGUUGUCUGUCUAGUCUGUUGAUAGUUUCUUUUGCUGUGCAGAAGCUUUUAAGUUUAAUUAGAUCCGCCUGUCAAUUUUUGCUUUUGUUGCGAUUGCUGUUGACAUCUUCGUCAUGAAAUCUUUGCCAUUCCUAUGUCCAGGAUGGUAUUGCCUAGGUUAUCUUCCAGGGUUUUGAUAGUUCUGGGUUUUACAUUUAAGUCUUUAAUCCAUCUUGAGUUGAUUUUUACAUAUCAUAUAAAGAAGGGAUCCAGUCUGAAUCUUCUGCAUAUGGCUAGCCAGUUAUCUCAGCACCACUUAUUGAAUAGGGAGUCCUUUCCCCAUUGUUUUUUUUUUUUGUCAGCAUUGUUAAAGAUCAGAUGGUUGUAGGUGUGUGGCCUUAUUUCUGGGCUCUCUAUUCUGUUUCAUUGGUCUAUGUGUCUAUUUUUGUACCAGUGCCAUGCCUUGAACAGGUUUUUAAUGCAGGUGGAAUUGACUCAUUCUGGAAAAAAAAAAUGCCACAGAGGACACUUAUUAGUAAGGAAGAGAAGUGAGCACCAGGAUUUAAGACAGGAAGGGCUAGGCUAACCCUAUUAUUUUGUGCCAGUGCAGUUAGGUUUAUGAUCAGGGCUGCCCUUAUCUAUAAAGCUGCUAACCUCUGAGCCUCAAAAGGAAAAGAUAAACACCAGCUGCCAGUCUUUGGGUUGGACAACAAUAAAAUUUAGUGAUAACCCCUUUUCUGGAUUGGGUCCACUGACGUGUUUUCCUUGAAGUCAGGAAGUACCUUACCAAUAAGGUACUGCCUUUCAAAAUUCUUUCGAUAUUGGACAAUGCCCCUGGCCACCCAGAACCAUAUGAGUUCGACAUGAAAGGUGCUGAACUGGUCUUCUUGCCCUCAAACACAACAUCUUUAAUGUAUCCUCUAGAUCAGGGGGUUGUGAGGACCUUUAAGGCUCAUUAUGCAGGAUACUCUAUGGAAAGGAUUGUCAGUGCUAUGGAAGAGAACCCUGGUAGAGAAAAAAUCAUGAAAAAGCUGUUAAAGCUAUCAAGCCCAAAAGAAAUUCCUGCUGGAGAAAAGCUGUGUCCAAAUGUUGUUCAUGACUUCACGGAAUUUAUGACAGAGUCAAUCAGGAAAAUCAUGAAAGAGAUUGUGGAUAUGGCAUAAAAGAUGAGGGAUGAAGGGUUUCAGAUAUGCACCUCAGAGAAAUUCAAGACCUUGUAGACGCCACACCAGAGGAAUUAACAGGAGACAACUUGUUGGAGAUGAGUGCUUCUGAACCAGUGCCAGACGAUGAGGAAGAAUUAGUAGAAGAAACUGUGCCAGGAAACAAAUUGACAUUAGACAACAUGGCAUAAGGAUUUUGAUUAUUCAAGACUGCUUUUGGCUUUUAUGACAUGGACACUUCUAUGAUGCGGGCACUGAAACUAAAGCAAACAGAGGAAGAAGGAUUGGUACCAUAUGGAAACAUUUUUAGAGAAAAAAAAAUCAGAAAUUACGAUGUAUUUCCAUACACUAAUACUGAGCCCCCUAAGUACUUCUCAUGGGAAGAGCCAAAGAAGUUUGUCACUGCCACCCCUAAGACAGCAAGACCAUUCCCACCUCUUCCUCCUUUUCCUCAGCCUACUCAAUGUGAAGAUCACGAGGAUGAAGACUUUUCUGGUGAUCCACUUCCACUUAAUGAAUAGUAAAUAUAUUUUCUCUUCCUUAAUAACAUUUUCUUUUCUCUAGCUUACUUUAUUGUAAGAAUACAGAAUAUACUAUAACACAAAAUAUGUGGUAAUGACUGACUAUGCUAUUGGUAAGGCUUCUGAUCAACAGCAGGGUAUUAGUAAAGUUUUUUGGGAGUCAAAAGUUAUAUGCAUAUUUUUGACUGUGAGGGGAUCAGUAUUUCUAAGCUCUGUGUUGUUCAAAGGUCAAUUGUACUAUUAUUUGCUAAAUCUGGUAACCCUAGAUGGAAGUGAUGUUUCUUAAAAAAGACAGGAAGGUGGGUAAUAGUCAGGUUGGGAGAAGGCAGACAUAAUGAUGCAGUGGAGCUGAAUUGCUUGAGAAUAAGAGUUUGAGGUAAUAUUAAGGGAAUAUGUUUAGCCCAGAGUGGCAGGCUCGUGAGUAGUGGAAAUGAGGCGAACAUUAGAGUAGGAGGUGGGGUGAAGAAUUAUACCAGGACGGGGCAGUCUUGCCAGGAUUGUUCCUUGUAAUUUCAUUAAGGAAGAUGGUUUGUCAAUGCCUUUACCAACCUCUGCAGCUUCUUCUGAAGGAUAACUUAUUUUUUAGGAUACAUGAAGUCUCUUGGUUUCAACUGGCCACUGUUUGGUAAUCUGCAUAAUUUCACCAUAUGUCCUUCUAACCUCAUCUGCUAGAAGGAAGGGAAAAGAUUGAUGGAUAAAUAUGGUGUAUGUUCAUGAAUGCAUUUUGUGAUGCCUUGGGAAAAAAGCAUGUCAGGAUAUAUAUAUUUUUUUAAAGUUAACUUUAGGAUCUAUUAGGAAAAAUAGGCAGAUAUAUGCUAGGAUGUUAUUUUGAGUAUUAGAUUUAUCAGUAUGUGUUGCUUUUUAUUCUCUUGAUAUUUGAAACAAUUUCCUUUUAUUUUCUAUUUUGACUUUAAUAAUUAUAGGUGUAAACAUCUAAUACAUUUCACUCAAUGAAUAACUGAUAAUUUAAAAUUUUUCUGUUGUUAAGAUUCCUGAUUAGUAUUUUUUUUCCUCCUGAAUUGUGCUCCUGAACAUAGAUAUAAUUAGUUUAAUGCAAAUGAGAAAAGUCUUUUCUUAGAAUCUUUGUGUUUUAAACUAUGUGAUAUUGAAAAAACCAACUUUAGUUAUUAGAAAAAAGCCACAGAAAGAAAAACUUCAAAGGCUACUGUGAUGUCAGCACCUGCUGUGGUCAUAGUGUAAACCCUGGAGACCAGGGAUUUUGGCAGCAGUUUUAGUGCUUUUAGUUCAAUCUUCAGUAUCCCCAAAUGUGAAGCAGAUGCCAGUUUUCUUCUCUAGGCUUCUGAUAAUGGCAUAUAAUGAGUUGGUUGUUUCCUAGCAACUAAAGAAGCAGUUUCACUUUAGCUGAUCCUGCAAUAGAAAUGAGACAUUUUCCCUUGAUAGUUGUUAUUAGUGAUUUCCCUGACAAUGGAAUUUCACUUUUGAAUAAGGAAUAUUCUCAGCUUUUGGUUUCCUAAAGAAUUUUGAUUCUGAGUUGCGCUAAGCUCUGCUUAAUCCUGUAUAAAAUGAAAAAAAGAAAUUGAGUCCCCUAAGUACCUCUCAUGGGAAGAGCCAAAGGAGUUUGAUACAUAGUUUCUUAAAUGGCAAGUGAUUAUACAAGAAGCUGUAAUAGGUGUAUUUUCUCAGUGUUUAACAGAAUAAUUAAUGACCACAUUCUUUUUUUUUUCCCUGCUUAAUAUUUGCAGCAGUAGAGGUUUCUUAGGUAAUGGCCAAUGUAUGUCGAAAUAAAUAUUGUAAGUUUUUAUUACAAGUGCCAUUUUGAUAUAAAGUCAGUAUAAGGAAAACAUAUUUUAAAAUCUAUAACCCAUUUGAUUUCAAACAGUAUUCUGUAUUAGAAAUUAUUAUUAUACCCAAUGAUUUUAAAGGCUCUUAAAAUAGUUCACUUUAAGGUGAAUUGUGAAACAAUUCAGUGUUUAAAUAUUAGUAGUUGUAAGGCAUCCAUAAUUGACUGAAUCAUAUCUAAAUCCUUCUAAUUUGAAAGUAGUAAUAGAUCUGGAUAUAUUCAGCCUCUUAAGAUAUAUGGAGGCAUGAGAAAAAUACUUCAGACGACCUUCUUUGUAGUCAUUCAUAGUUUAAAUAGUUUCUAAGGAAAUGAUCCAUUUUUCUUCCUUUGACAUUAUAAAACUAAUAUAAGUUACCAUCCUCAUCCACCUCAUCCAAAUUUAUGGUAUGAUAUAUUAAGUUAUGCCUAAGUGUCAGAGAGAUAAAAUAUUAAAUUAUGUUCUUAAGAUAUUAAGUUAGCCAUAUCUAAAUAUACCAAAGAAAUUUAUUACCUUGCAUGGAAAAGAUUCAUAGACUAUGCAUUAACUAUAGGUGAAGUCAUUGAAUAUUGUUAUUGUCAGUUUGGGGCAUGUGACCUUAUUAAUUUCUUUUUAUGAUUUUUGCAUCAUCAGGUACUCUAGCAGGCCUCAUAUUUUAAAAAUGCUUUAAACAUUAAGGAAUGAGGAACAUUAAUUAAUUCAGUUUUCAGUUGGACAGGGCGGUAGCCUUUUAGGCACCUAAGACAAAAUUAAAAAAAAAAAAAAAAAAAAAAACCUUUAAACA